CAAAGGAGCCAAGACCAUGGCGAAAGCCGGGGAUAAGAGCAGCAGCAGCGGGAAGAAAAGUCUAAAACGGAAAGCCGCUGCCGAAGAACUUCAGGAGGCUGCAGGCGCUGGGGAUGGGGCGACGGAAAACGGGGUCCAACCCCCGAAAGCGGCUGCCUUUCCGCCAGGCUUUAGCAUUUCGGAGAUUAAAAACAAACAGCGGCGACACUUAAUGUUCACGCGGUGGAAACAGCAGCAGCGGAAGGAAAAGUUGGCAGCUAAGAAAAAACUUAAAAAAGAAAGAGAGGCUCUUGGCGAUAAGGCUCCACCAAAGCCUGUACCCAAGACCAUUGACAACCAGCGAGUGUAUGAUGAAACCACAGUAGACCCUAAUGAUGAAGAGGUCGCUUAUGAUGAAGCUACAGAUGAAUUUGCUUCUUACUUCAACAAACAGACUUCUCCCAAGAUUCUCAUCACAACAUCAGAUAGACCUCAUGGGAGAACAGUACGACUCUGUGAACAGCUCUCCACAGUUAUACCAAACUCACAUGUUUAUUACAGAAGAGGACUGGCUCUGAAAAAAAUUAUUCCACAGUGCAUCGCAAGAGAUUUCACAGACCUGAUUGUUAUUAAUGAAGAUCGUAAAACCCCAAAUGGACUUAUUUUGAGUCACUUGCCAAAUGGCCCAACUGCUCAUUUUAAAAUGAGCAGUGUUCGUCUUCGUAAAGAAAUUAAGAGAAGAGGCAAGGACCCCACAGAACACAUACCUGAAAUAAUUCUGAAUAAUUUUACAACACGGCUGGGUCAUUCAAUUGGACGUAUGUUUGCAUCUCUCUUUCCUCAUAAUCCUCAAUUUAUCGGAAGGCAGGUUGCCACAUUCCACAAUCAACGGGAUUACAUAUUCUUCAGAUUUCACAGAUACAUAUUCAGGAGUGAAAAGAAAGUGGGAAUUCAGGAACUUGGACCACGUUUUACCUUAAAAUUAAGGUCUCUUCAGAAAGGAACCUUUGAUUCUAAAUAUGGAGAGUAUGAAUGGGUCCAUAAGCCCCGGGAAAUGGAUACAAGUAGAAGAAAAUUCCAUUUAUAAAGUACUGAGAGAAUGAUAUUGGAUUUUGCUGAACAGGCCUAUCUUGAACUUUGGUAAAUUAUUUUUGACAGAAUACUCUUUUCAAAAUGGCAUUUGCUGAUUUCAUAAACCUUUCACGUCUGGACGAAUUACCAAAUGCCAUGAAUUGCCACUGUGUGUUUAUGUAGAAAAUACAAAUAAAAGUUAUUUUGAUGGCUUAGGUUUCCUUAAACUUAGUUCUCUUGUUUUUGGGUAACUGUGAAUAAUUAAGUUGGAAUCAAGAUUCAGAUUAACUUUCCUAUUUGCAUAGAACACAUGAGAGGAAUAAAAUGGUUGGUAAAUAUUGGCUAACCCUUGAUUUUUAUACCAGAUUAACCUUGGAUUCCCAGUGUCUGGCACAGUUUUAAUAGCUUAAAUGGAGGCCAGGUUUCUGGAUGUUUUAACAUUCUCUUAAGCCUUCAGAAGGGUAAAAAAUUUAAAGCAAAAUGAUCUACCAGGGUUUAAAGCAAAGUUGCAAAUUACUGAAGCUAAUCUUUGCUUCCUGAUUUUGAGGUUUUUGGUUUUUUGUGCCCACGUUGUGGGGAGCUCUUUUUUACCUCAUUACAUGGUGCUGUAGUACUCCAUUCAGGCACUGAAACAAAGUUAACCCUAUAAGUAACUCAUGGAUGGAAACCCGUAGAACUUAACAGCCUCCUCCUGACCUUAAAAGAAUAAAGGUUCACAGUUUACCUUUAAUUCCCUAGCAGUCUUGCCAGAUGUAUGGCAUAAAGUCAUGUGAGAAGAGUAGGUGGAAAAAACUGUACAAACUUAACCCCUUCAGGUGUUCAGAACAGAUUAAUAUACCAUGUAUUUAAUACCAAUAAUAAUGCAAAAUAAAAGUUUCAUACUAAGUUUUAUUGUAUG